CUUCUCCUUCGCCUUUUCUCUCUUGCUUCUUUCUCUGCUUCACUUCAUUCUCCCUGUUCUGUCCUCUCUUCCAGUCGCCCUUUUUUCCAACCCACCCUUUGCUAUGUUCUGAAUUAGUGAUUGCCUAAGUGGAAAGAUGGAGACAGUUUCAGAAAUCCUAUUUAUUUUAGUUCAUCAGUUGUUACUGCUUACUUUUUGUUUGAAUAUAUUUGGGGUAUAUUCUCAAAAAUAUGUUGAUAAUGGAGUACAGAAAUUCUGGUGACUGUUACUCUCCAAUGUCUCUCUUUUCUUCCUAGAACUAACUACUAGUCCUUUCCAGUUCGGGUAGAUGGAUUAUAUUUCUUGCAUAGUACUUUCAGCAUUUAUCAUUUUUGGUAAAUGAAUACCUAAUGUGCCGCUAGGGAAGCUAAAUUCAUACCUAUUUCAGCUGGGGUGAGCACUGUGACCUUCUGUUACACAUACCUAUUGCUGCCACCAGAGACAGAAGAUUGAGUUGGAUGCACUAUGGGUAGAGACAAGGGCUGGUGCUACUUACUUAUCAGAAAGGAUUCUUGUAAGAAUUAAAUGAAAUAAUGGGCAUAGAAUUUAGAAUUAAAUAAUGUUAUGUGCAUGGUAUGCUACAAAGAUUUGGAUUCAGACCUCUUUACAAAUCUCAGAUUCGUCAUUUACUAGCAUGCAAACUUGGGCAAGUCACUUUAUUCUACUUGAACCUUUUCUUUUCUAUAAAAUGAGGUCAAUAAAUAAUAUUCAUUUACAAAUUGAUCAUCAAGGCAAAUGAGAUAAUACAUGAAAUCUCCUAAAAUAGAGUAGAUGCUCACUGAAUAUCACCUUACUUCCCUCCACCCAACUAUGCAUUUAUUUAUCUGUCAAACAUUUAUAUUAUGCUCACUUUAUGCCAUGCACUGUUCUAAGAGCUUUAUAAAUUUAACUCUUCAAUAUCAUCAUAGUCUUUUGAGUACUUACUAUUACUAUCUCGUUUUGCAGAUUGGUAAGCUGAAGCAAAGGAGGUUUAAUAACUUGUUUAAAGCCUCAUGGAUAGUAAGUAGCAGAGCCACUAACUGAUAUUUUUGUGCCGACACCUUAAUUCAAGCUUUUUUCUCCUUUAACUGAAGAUAUUAUUGCCCUGAGAUAUUACCUUGAAAUCGAUAUAGAUUUUUUUCUUGAGUUUGCAAAUUUUCUCUCUUAGAAGGCCUGAGGAAAAAAUAACAUUAAACAAAUGCACACUUAAUUAUGAGUUCAUUUUCUGUGUUAAUGUAGUAAAGAGGUGAAUGAAUGUCAUAAAAUAUACUCUCAUUUGGUUCCACCCUGAGAGAGCCGUUGGAUUGCAGCCCCAGUGCUUUUCAGCAGGGAAGCUGGCCAGAGAUGCCUGCAGCCUGCUGGGGAGUGUGUGGGUAGCUCCUCCAGCAGUGUGCCUGCACUCCUCAUCUGCACAGAGCAUGCACAGUGUUCAAAGGCACACAGAUGGGGACUCAAGUGGGGCCAAGAUCACUGGGAAGAGUGUCGGAAAAUGAAACCUGGCCAACAGACAGCACCCUUCUGUUUAAUCAGAAUGCUGGAGCCAGGUCCAGAGAAUAAUGACUACAAACUGGCUGUGCCUUGGGCCUAUUCAGCAUCUUGUUCUCAUUUUCAAGUGUUUGGUCCUUGGGAAGGUCUCAAAGUUCACUUUGCUACUCGAUUAUGCUGCCUAUUGAGGAAUUUUCAAGGCAAAGUGAAUUCAUGUGACCUGGAUUCAUUAUUAUUUAAGAUUAUUAACACAUUUUUAGACCGAAUUGGCAGUAAGGAAAGGGAGGAAGGAAACAUCUAUUGAGGUCAUACCAGGUGCUGGGUGCUGUAGUGGGCACUUCUAUGCAUGUUAGCUCAACUGACGAUACCAGAGAAGUGGAAAUUACUUCAGAUUGUCAUGAAAAAGACAAAUGGAGAAGGUGGGAUGCAUGAAAAAUAGACUUUUAAAAUUCCUAAAUCAAUGCCCUCAAGUCAUCUAAAAUGAUUAGAAACAGUCUAUAGUUGUCUUUUAUGAGGAGACAAGAAUUAUAUGUGUUCCUUGUUUUUUUCUCCUUCUGCUUGCUGAAGAGUUCUGGUUUCACUUGUCUAGUCCUUUUCCUUCCCUUUGUCCUGCCUUGAGAGACUGGUUAUAUUAAGCUUUUGUGAGGAAUUUCAGGUGAGAGGGAAUGGAGGAAGAAAAAAGAGACUUAGGGACACAUAUUCAUACCCAUGUGUGUAUGUGUAUUUAUGUGAUAUAUGUAUAAUUUUAUAUAUGUGAUAAAUACAUACACAUUACAAAUGCAAUUAUACUAUACUUAAUCUUUCAUAUGUUUUAAAUCCUUCAAGUUUAUUAUGAACAUCUCCCCAUGUCAACACAUUUAAAACCACAGUAUCAUUAUUAAUAUUGCCUAAAACUCUAUACUCAGUAUAUGUCAAUACUUGAUUAUUGGAUAUUUAGGUAGUUUCCAGUUUUAGUUUUAUCAAUAGUGCAGCAGUGACAUCUGAACAAAGUCAUUUAAAAUGGCACCAGUUACUGUUUCUCAGGGAUCAGCUUUAUUGUGAUUUUUCUUAAAUUAGAGGAAUCGCCUAUAUGUUCAAACUAAUUUUUUAGAUUACUAGAAAUAUUCUUGUAACAAUGUCUUAUGGAGAACCCACUGUAUAAAACCCAUAGAAGUGUACUUCCCCAGCCAGAUGCAGUGGCUCACACUUGUAAUCCCAGCACUUUGGGAGGCCAAGGCAGGUGGAUCACUUGAGGUCAGGAGUUCCAGACCAGCCUGGCCAACAUGGUGACAUCCCAUCUCUACUAAAAAAAAAAAAAAAUUCAAAAAUUAGUUGGGCCUGGUGGCACACACCUGUAAUCCCAGCUACUUGGGAGGCUGAGGCAGAAGAAUUGCUUGAGCCCGGGAGGUGGAGGUUGCAGUAAGCUGAGAUCAAGAUCACGCCACUGCACUCCAGCCUGGGCGACAGAGCUAGACUGCCUCAAAAAGAAAAAAAAAAGUGGUACUUUCCUCCAUGGGUUGCCUCCUGCCCCUGAACGCCCCCAUCCCUCAGUGACCUCUGAGCUUCCACAGUACCCAAGAGUGCUCCGGAACAAUGGUAAGACCACUGAGCUAGGAACUAGCUUUGUUUUGUUUGUUUGUUUGUUUCUAUAUUAUUAUUUGUUGAUGUUACAGAGUAUAGAAAAUUGGCUUUUUUUCUUUAAAAGAAGAAACUAUGUUUUCUUUUUUUAAAACAACUCACAUUGAGCUUUGCUAUACUACUUUGUUACCUGAAUUGGUAAUGGUUUUCUUUUUUUCUAUGUUAUAAUAGAAUCUUUAUAUUUAAAUAAACUUAAAUACUUUCAGGCGCUGUGGUCUAGAGCUCACUGAAAGUGUUAUGUGUACAUGAGCAGGACCCUCAAGAGCCAACCUGUGUUUUUUGUCUCAUUAACUUGGAGGAAGGCAUGAGGGGUCAGGGCCUACAAUAUCACUUGGAAACAAGGAAUAUAAAGAAAAUCUGGCCUGUUUGGUAAAACUGUGCUUCUCCAUGUCUUGCCUCUUUUGAUCUCUUGCCUAAGUUUUGUUUUGAAAGGUUAACACUAUUCAUCUUGUCAUGACUUUAAAUAAUCAGAUUACUUUUCUAUGCAACAAUGCUCUGUUUUUCCUAAGUUUCCUAUUUCUUCAGUGAUUCUGGGGUGGGAUGGAGAGUGAAUAGAAAUACAGGCAUCAACUUUAGUGUUUUCAUUGCAAUUGUUUUAUUUGUGCCCCUCAAGUUGAACCUCUCUGAAUGAGUGUGAUCAUAUAUCUCACAUACUUGGUGUUUUUUCUUCAGAUGUUGGGAUUCAAAUUGUUUGGAAAUUUCACAUGUUGUAAACCUAACUUAGUGACAUCAUGUGACCAUGUAUAAGGGAACCUUUAUCAUUAUGUUAUUAGGAACCUGAUCUCUUUGUCAUUCAUCUAUUUUUUGCCCUGGCUUGUUGGGAUUGGAUCAAACCAAUGGAAAUGCCGGAGAACUGAGUUAGAAAUGCAUAGGAUGUUAAAAGAACAGAAAUUUAUGCUUUAAAGUAUUACUACUAUUAGAUUUGUAAGUUUAAUUUUUUUUCCUCUGGUGUUAAAUAAAUUGCUCAAAGAUCUCUGACACCAGAAGGAAAUUAGAAGGUAAAUGUAUGUUGAUAACACAGAAGGAUCAGAGAGGGAAAUCCACUAGCAAAUAAAAGAAAAUAGGAAGAGUAAGUAAGUACAUCAUUGUAAGCAAAAACUGACAAAAAGGAAAGUUUGAAGCCAGAAACAGUCAAAAAGUUCUUCUAAAAGUAAGAAAAUGUUUAUGAGGGGCACAUUGGACAUAUUUUCUAUUCUAUUGGGGUCUGGAGAGAUAGGCAAGUAUGAAUGAACAGGUGGAAUUUAGUUGUUUUCCAAAACUUGAACAAACAAGAAAGGGUAUUUUGGGGUCCAAUUAGCAACAUUAAGAUAAAUUUUAUAUACUGGCUUCCUGGGAUUUGUGCCUUCAAUUUACAAGUUUUGCUGAUAAAGAAGAAAAUCAAUUUUAUUUUAUUCUAUUUCCCAGGGAGAUAGCAAAAUGCUUGAGGAUUUUUUUUGCAAGAGACUUUUUAAUUAGGACUAUUAUAGAAAUGAGUUAAACAGCCAAAUAUCAAACCUGAAACGAUCUCCUGAGGCAAGAGUGUACAUGAUCAUUAGGUUUGGAGGCAAACUAUUGUUAAGGAUUCUCAUAUAAGGUAUCUUAGUCUCCACAAGCAAAGGUGAUCAAAUCCAGUUGAACUUGCUUCACACCAUAUGCCAUUGUCCUUCAGUCCCCCAAGCAGACAAAUCAAGCUUGAUUACAUAUGAGAUACCAAGGCAUCCAGAGAAAUGAUAGUGGGUGUAAGUCAUGCCACAAUAGGGUGUGGAUAGGUGUUUCUGGAUACGGAGAUAGAUGGCCACACAAUCCUGCUGCCUUCACCCAGCCAGCUCUCAGCUUAAGAGAGGUAGGAAAUGAGGCAAGGAAAGGAAGAUCUGAGCCCUUCCUGGAGCUCAGCUGCAUCCUGAGGCAGAUGUUUAAUGGACUAGAAAUGAUCACAUAGAGAAUUCCUUGUGUCUAACCUAGAACUAAAGCCUGUGAGAACACACUCUUAAUUUAUUUCCAUACUGAAGCCCUAACCAGAAGCUUAGAUCUUUGCAUUCCAACAUAAGAAAGAGACAGGGGUUACCAAACUAAUCUGUGAGAAGUAAAAGAAUGUGUGAAAAAAAUAACAUGAGCCCCAGAGUCUAGAGCAGAAGUGGAUAAGAUGACCUUACCUAUAGUCUUCUAAGCUGAGACAACAGGAGGCCAGGCCCCUGGUCGGGAGGAUGGUGUGUGUGUGUGUGUGUGUGUGUGUACAUGUGUGUGUAAUGUGACUUACCCAUUAGGCACCAUAGGUGCGGUGCCUUGGGGCCGUGGCAGUUUUAGGGCUCCACAAAAAUGUUUUAAUCUUUUUUAAAAUCAAGAAUAAAAAAUGAAUCUAAUAAAAAUAAUGAAUAUUUAUUAAUGAAUUCAGCAUAGAUUAUAUAAACUUGCCUUAUGCCAAUGUAGUCCUAAAAUAUGUUUUCAUAUUUUUUUCUAUAGAGGAAGGUACUCAUGAGGGCAGAAGUGACUAGGGCCAAAAAAGUCAUUGUGCAGCUCUGACAGAUUGAAUGACCAUGAGAGAGACACAGAAUGACAACCUCCUGAUAGAUAGAUGCAGAGAGAUUGGCAGAGAGGAACAGAGACAGAACAGCGAGAAACAGAUACAGGAAGAUACAUGCAGAGUGAGAAACAGGGACAGAGAGACAGAGGGAGAUGAAAACAGACACACAUGCCCACACACAAAGAGAGAAACAGGCAGACACACACCCCCGCGCCCCCUCCCCCAUCUGGACCCGCCCCACCAACAUCCUGACAGAUACAGGAAGGCAGAGAGAAUGAGACAGAUGGAGACACAGGAAAGACAUGCAGAACUAGACUGACAGCCAUAGGCUAAGAUGUCACAGGGAACAUUCUACUGGAAGGAGGCAGCCAUCAGCUUGGUCUUACUUGUUUCAGCCUCCCAGGAUCAAAUAUGUCUGAAGAGUAACAGGCCUUUCCAUCCACUCUUUAUUUUUAGCCACAGAGGAAACAGUAAGAGAGAAGAGGGCAGAUGCUUCUGUUUACCAGGAUUUUAAUUGGCUACCUUUGGAGCCUGUGGGCCUAAGCUAUGACUAUUGUCUAGAAGCUUUGGGAGAAAGGUAAAACCACAGUGUAAAAUCACAGUGGAAGCUUGGAGCUGAAAUGAUUAUUGUAUCUUCUCUAACCUUAUACCCAGUAAUGAUGUGUUUGUAAGGCCAGUGGUCCAAUUUUUUCUGCAGAGUGAACAAACCAGUGGCUCCCCCACUACCUCCAUAGAGAUGUUUUAACACAGACACAUUCUAAACAGCAAACUACAUCGGACGCCAGUCUCCUAUAAAUGCUAGAGAGUAGGCCUCCUCCUGGCCUUUAUUUUUCCAUGUUCCUGGAUAUAUGAGAGUCUCAAGAGGGAGGUUUGAUGCCAACCCCUGCCCUUGACCUUGGGCAACCUUCUUCCCCUUUGUGGGUGGAAUGAGGUGCCAUGACUUGUUGCUUUUAUUCACAAAGUGCCUCACUUGUUUAUAUGAAGCCACCGGCCUCAUGGCCAUGCCUCAGCCAAACCAACUGGGAAUUAUGAAGAUUGGUUUGAGGCAGGAAGUGUCCUGGCUCUAGACCUAGGACAGCUGCUUUGAUUGUGAGUGCACCAGGAAAGUGGGACAAUUGAAGCAUGAGGACCUUGUCAUUUAAUUGAAAGUCACAGAGUUCCUUUUCACCUGUGUCAUCUCUGGAAAACUGGAGAGAGAUGAUCUAUACAAGACCCAGUAAGAUACACACCAUUUAAAAUGCCCUACAAGAAGUCACAGUGAAAUGAAAUAAUUUACACCAAAAGGUGUAUGUUCUUCAAUCUUCUCUGAAUUCUGGACUUCUGAUCUUGCCAGAGAUAGUUGUUAGAAGAAAUUGAUGAUAACUUUUUUAAAAAGAAACAAGUUUUAAAACUAGAACUAGCUCAGCCUUCCCUUCAUUCAAGGUUGGAUAAGCAGUAGUCAGUGAGAACUUGGGAAAAUAGUCUUGAAGAGGAACUGUGUUCACAUGUCCUUAGUCAUGAAAAUCAUUUUUAGGUGAAGUGAUUUCUCAUUUUGCACAAAUGAUUAUAGAGUGUGUCUGUUUGUGAACUUGGUCAUAAUUGCUGCCCAACAUCAUUAUGGCGAUAAUUUGUUUAGCUAAGAGAAUAAGAGCAGUUGAAGUUAUUUUUAAGUUUGCAUUUUGUCAGUUGUAGGUUUUCUUUUUUCUUCCUUUUUUUUUUUUUUUUUGCAUUUGAUGGCACCAGCUGAGUGUGGGAUGGUGCACAAAUCCCCUCAGAAAUGGAGUUAUUUGGUCACAGUAAACUGAAGCCUCUCCCCAACCGCCAAGAUAACAGCAAUUACUUUGGAUUCAUUUUAGUAGGUGUGAAAAGCUCAUCUGUUUAAAAGAUGAGUACUCUGGUUUAUAUAGGAUCCUCUGGUAGCAGCAGGUUAAUUAAAGAAUGAUUCUAUCAUCCCUAGCCUAAAUCGCAGGCAUUAUAAAAGCCAGCCUGCUUUAUGACUGUCAUGUGAGAAAUGUGCACACUGAUACCCCAGAAUUUGAGCAUUGUUAAAAGUUAGUCCAUUGGGUGUGUUUGUUCUUCACAUUAUCCAGAGCAUCUGCCAGUUUCUUCUUUCUUGAUUAUAUGCACCUUUGCAAACAAUAGUACAGUUAGCAACACUCUUCUAAGUGUGCCACAUUUAAUUUGGGGUGAGAAUACAGCUUUAAUUCCAUUUUACAGAUGAAGAAAUGGAGGCACAAAGUUGUUAAGUACCUUUGUCCAAGGUCCUAGAGUUUGUGAGCAGCAGAAGGGGUUUAGCAAUCAGCCUGCCUUGGGAGCCAUGUGCUUAUUACCUACAAUUCACUGCCCAACUGAGAAGUAGCAUGGGAGAUCACCUCUCCCACUCAUCUUUGAGAUGCUGAUUCAUUAUUUGACUAAGAGGCCAGACUCUUCUGCUUACCAGGAUUUUAAUUGGCUACCUUUGGAGCCUGUGGGCCUAAGGUAUGACUGUUGUCUAGAAGCUUUGGGAGAAAGGUGAAAUCACUGUAAAAUCACAGCGGAAGCUUGGUGCUGAAAUGAUUAUUGUAUCUUCUCCAACCUUAUACCCAGUAACGAUGUGUUUGUAAGUCCAAUUUUGUGUUUGUGGUCCAAUUUUUUCCUGCAGAGUGAAAAAAAUAAUGGCUCCCCCACCACCUUGAUAUGGAUGUUUUAACACUACACAUUCUAGACAGCAAACUACAUCAGAGACCAGUCUCCUCAUCCCUGGAGGCAUCACACUGUGUGCUGGGCUCUGGACAAAGUAACUAGAAGUAUAAGUUCUAAGCAGUCCUCACCACUAAGUAACUUGUGGUAUAAGAGAGGGAAUGGCACACAUAAUUGUCAAGUCAACCCUUACUGCAAAGAAGUUCAGAUGGGUGGUGCAAGCAGUAACUGCUGUGGAAGCUCAGAUGAGGAAGAAAACAGGUCUGGCUGAAUGGUAUGGGUCUCCAAGAAGAGGGCAGGAUGUGUGCUUGUCUGAGUUUGGGGAUAAGAUUCAAUUUUAUUCUAAAAAAAAUUGCACUUGGAUGAAUAGAGAGAAGAACAUGCCAUGUGCAGAGAUGUGAGCAGGACUCUGUGAAUGUAAAACACAGGUGAUGGUCAGAGUCAGAUGGGAGAGCUCUAUUUUGGGAGUCCUGGAUGAGAGGCUGAAAAGAUACCCACCGACCCAUGCUCUAUUAUAGCGAGCAGAAAAAUGAACACAUUGUGGUUUGCUCAUUUCAUAUAUGAAAGUGUGGGGCUCAAAAAUCUGAUUACUGUGUAUGUCACGUAGAACCACACUUCCCCCUCCAAAGUACGUCUCAUGCCAUUGUAUAUUCACAUCUUGUCUAAGAAGAAACUGUAUCUCUAAGUGCCAUAAACUCCAAUAAAAGCAGGUUUGUUCUUUCCUCCCACUUGUGUUCCUGAAACCUAUGUUUAUAGGACCUUAUGUUACUUACACUUUGGUGUGUUACCUUUAAUCUCAACCUCUAUUUGCUACAAACACCACUGAAAGGUGACAGUUUCAUGUGGGAUAAACUCUAUUGAUCUCUGUCUGUAAGGCAAGAUGUUUUUCUCAAGCAUUUUUGGGCACAUUUUCUCUGAGAGGUAGCAUAGGGCAGUGGUCAUGAGCAUAGAUGGAAGUCAGACUGUCUGGGUUCUGAUCCCAGCCCUGGCACUUAUUGCUAGGCAACCUAUGGUAUGUACUUAACUUCUCUGUGCUUCCGAUUACUCAUGUUUUUAAAGAUUAAAUUCAGGCACCAUGCUUUAAGAAGCACCUGGCACAUAGUAUGGAAUAGUUAGCUUACAUCAUGGGUUCCCAGCAGGGGUGAUAGCACCCUCAAGGGGGCAAAAAGUUUAAAUUCAGGAAUGGUUUCAUUAGGAAAACAUUUGCUUAGUGAGGCUUCUUGUGGGGCUGAGGGGUAAGAGGGAUGAGUGGAGAGGAAAAAAGUGGUCCAGAAACCCCUGGGUUGCACCAACCCCAUUAAGUUGGACCUGAUGAAGCAUUGAUAGAAGGAAUCCCAAAAGAGGUUUACAUGUUGUACUUGGAGGCCCGUAACCAAUAGAGGGUUUAAUCAACAGGCUUUUUACCUAGGGCCUGAUGUAGGCUCCGCCUUAAGGCCAUCACAUUCACUGCUUGGUUAUGUGCACAGGGAGGGAACCAGUGGAAGCCCAACCCCCCUUCCACAGGGUUCUUGAAGCUAGUCAUGAAGGGAACAGAGGGAGGAGGGAAUGAGUUGCUUUGCCUGCCUUGCCUGAGGUGGAAAUGGCUGUGAUAGAUGUGGUGUGACCUGGGCAGAGUGAAUAGUAAAAGUUCACAUCUACCCAGGAUUUUCUGUUUUUCAGAGUAGUUUCACACUCAUUAUCUCACAAGCACUCUUUCUCUUUUGAAAUAGUUUUUAGUUACACAUGUAGUAAAGAAAUGCAUUCCUUUGUAAGAAAUUGAAGUAUUACUGAUAAAAGUAAAAAUGCCCCAUGAGCCACAUCUGGUUCCAGUUCCCUGCUCCCUCCACAGGAUUAACCCCUGUUAGCACUGUGUGUGUCCAGCACUUGUUUCUAUUCAUUUAUGCUCAGGUAAGACUAUUUUAAAAAGUACACUAUUGCUGUGUAGAUCCUUUAACACUAAGGAUAUCAAACUAUAUGUAAUUUUCUACUUCAAGCUUUUUUUAAAAUCAUAAUAUGUCUUGGAGAUGGUUCCAUAAUAAAACAUUCAGAUCUACCUCACUCCUUUCAAUGACUGCAUGCCCAUGGAAUGAAUACCUCAUUAUUUAUUUAGCCAUCUUACUUUCUGGUAAAUACUGAUAUUGUUUCUGUUUUGAUUUUUUUAACCACAGCUACGAAUGCCACCUCUUUGGGUAUGUGGGUACGUGUCUACAGCUGCUCAUUGAGGCAGAUAUUAUCUUUACAGCAAAGGAGACUGAGGCUCAGAGAGGUGACACAGGCAGUGAAUAGCAUGUCCAGGACCAGAAGCCAGGUCUUUUUUGUUUUAAAUCCAGGUUUGAUGGAUUUUCUUCCCUCAUUCCACAGCUACCUCCCACCCUUAUCUCAUACUGGGACAUUUGCAUUUGGCAACUGAUUUCCUAGCAGUAACAUCCCUGGGGUGGCCCUACAUGUCGCUGCUCCUUUUCUCACUGUAGAUGAUGGAUCAGCUGCUGUGUGUCCCUGAAGGAAGGCAGCUUUCAGGAGGUGGACAGCUGUGUGUGAAUAAAACAGGGGAGGAGGGGAUCCACACAUACCUGUCCUGACCUAUUUACCGAGCGAGCUGUUGAGCCAAAGCAGCACCGUGUUAUCUAACCACAGCUAAAAUUUGAAAGGUCCAACUGAGAAAUGUCAGGAGGAAGUAACACUUGAAUUAUUAAGGAAGUAGGUACUAAAGGAGAUGGAGAAGAAUAACCUAUGAAACCGGCUUGUUUUGAGCAGGAAAGGAGGAGAUGGAUGUUCUAAGUGACCGCCAUAACUUGAAAAUAAAGUGGUUCCUGGGGCCUACUAAAUGUUUAAAUUUCAGAGAAUCCAAGCUUCUUUUUGAUGAGCCUUCUUCAGUAUUUUACAACGGCAUAUCGAAAGGGUUUCUUAAUUAAAAUCCCCAGCACGUUGGAGGGGCGGGCUGAUUGAGGCUGCAGUGCCUGCAGGCAGGGUGCCCACCUCCAUCAGCCACGCCAGCCGAAGGGGCAUCCUGCAGCUCCUCUGUCAGAGGGAUUCCUGCCGGAGCACCUCCUGGCAGAGAGCAUGAGGCCCGGCCAAUUCAAUGUGGCCUCGCUGCCCCAGCCCAGCCGGGACACUCCCCAGGACCCAAUUAGCAGAUUGGAAAUCGCAUCCAAGUAUGUUACAAUCACCAAGUUAAAGAGGAAUAACAGACAUGAAAGAAUCAAGUGGGAAAAGAACAUUUUGGAUCCCGAAAGAGCAGGCUGCUUGUCGGAGUUCUAACGAACCGAAACAAAAUAAGUAGUAGCUCCUUAAGCCUCUUUUCUAACACUGCUGGGAUUGGUUAGUGUAGAGAAAAGCAUUGAAAUUGCAAAAGAAAAAAAUGCUUAUUGUUCCUAUGUUCAAUUUGUUAUUUAAUAUAACUUGUUUUUUAGGAAUUUAAUAAAAAAAAAGGGAGGGCAUCAUUAAUUUUACAUUCUGCAAGAAAAUGAAAAAUGAUCUGCUGAUUAGUGAUGUGCAAUUUGUUCCUUGAACAUCUCCAGUAAUGUGUGAAUGUCACAUUACAUAACACUUAUAAUGAUUAAACCAGAAGAUGAAAUAAGAUAGGAUAGAUCUUGUGUUCUUUCCUUGACUGGUGGACAACUCAUCUCAUUAAUCUCUCUUUGGCUUGCAGCCUUAAAUUGAAUAAGCCGUGUUACUGGGGGAGAUUUAUGGCCAAAAGACUUAGCAGCCUCACUGAGGAAAUCUUAUAGCACCAUUUUGAGAGCUCUCCAAGAUAAUUCUUGGGAUUUGUAUUAAUUGUAGCUUGUCAUAAAACAUUGCCCAAACCAGAAAUGAGCAAUGAACCUUCUCAGGAACUUAAUAUUACAGCAACAUUGAAAAUAUGCACUUCUUGAUGUUCCAUCUCAUGAGAUGUUAAAACAUUCUGAGUCCCAAUUUAAAAUUAUUAUAUUAGAAAUGGUAGCUUCAGUAGAGUGGGAAAUGAUAGCUUCAGUAGAGUGGGAAAUGAUACACUGAUACACCUGGGCACUGAGGAAUGUUUGUAGAAAACCAGUGGGCUUUCAAUAUCACAAGGGCAGUCCUUCGCAGAGCAGUGAGCAGGAUGUCCCUAUGAAAUGUUUGUAGAAAGAAUGAACCAACUGGUAACCAUGAGUCCUCUUUUUAAAAUAUAAGUUCUCUUUGUGGUUGAAUUUCUGACACUUGGUGUAUAAGUACCAGUAAGUAAGAUUGGCUUACUUGUUGCAAUUUUUAAAGGAAGUGCCUUGCCACAGCCAGAACCAGUGGCCUGGAACUAAAGUUGAAAAGAGGUUAGAUUUAAUAAGUCAUCCAAUAUAUACAAGAUUUCCCUUUAGCAGUCAUCAGUAAGCCUUGCUUGAUGACUUAUUCCAUUUGGGGUGUUCACUUCCUCUCACCGUAGCAUGUUUAUUACUGGACUCUGGGCUCCUUGAAUGCGAUUCUGUGCCCUUUUCUGUAGCCCCACAUGUCAGUUAUGCACAGGACACACUAAAUGCUCAACAAACACUUUCUGAUAUAUAAAACCAAAAUUAUUGUUUAUAUGAAGUCAAAAUCUACCUCCUUGAACUUCCAUUUGGUGGACCUAGUUCUAUCUUCUGCACAAAAAUAAACAUGUCAACUCCCUCUUCCCUGUGAGUAUUUUGAGGCUUAAUCACUCCUCAAGUCUUCUCUGUGCCAGAUUAAUCCCUAGUUCCCUAAAUUAAUUAUUUUCUUAAGCUGCCAUGUCAAUCAUUUUGUGCUUCCUGGUCAACUAAAACCUCAGGUUUUUCUUAAGUAAUAUAAAGGAAACAUUUCCCCUCAUCUUUUAUUGGAGUCAUGUUUUCCUUUUAAUCUUUUUAACUGAAUCCUACUUACCAUUUUCAAUUUUAAUGAUACUGCUUAACCAAUCUUUCUACCUUACUGAGAGUUUUUCAAAUGCUGAUUUUGCCAAUAAUGCUGUUACCAUGGUGUUGUAUCUUUUGCAGAUUUGAUCAACAGUACUGGCAUCAGAAAAACACAGAUGCUUUGGUAGGUGUCAUCAGGGUCCUCAUCUCUCCCUAUGCUGGCAUUGAUCUAUCACCUUAUGUGAUCUUUAGCCCCAUACAAAUUCUCAUAUGGCAUUAGAAGUAACUUUAGAAAAUAUUAAAUCCAUUUGUCCUCUCUAUUGAUACUAUACAUGAGGAAACUGAGUCCCAAAGAGCCCAUGGCCACAUUACUGGUUAAUAGAAACACUCAUAUUAGAACUAAGGUCCAAGUGACACCAAAGGCAGGUGUCCUUUCCUGUUUAUCAUAGCUGCCAGUCUUUAUAUUAUUCACAAGGUCAAUGCAAGAAACAUUUAAACAUCUCGUUGGAAUCCCAACAUAUUGUGAUAGGUUUCCUAUUACGUGAGGGUUAUGUACCACUGUCAAUUAGAAGAUAAAGCAAAGUGGUGGCCUUUUUUAUCUCUUAUUCUAAGAUCUUCAGUAAAAUUCCUUCUGUUUCUAAAUAUAAAGCUUUAAAACAGGCUAUAUUGAUGUUGCGAAAGAACUGGUACAUUAUAAGUAGAAGUGUGUGUGUAUGUGUGUGAGGGAGGGGUAUACACAUAUGCACGUGCUUUAUAUCAUAAUUAAAGAGUGGAAGAAACAGGAUUCUUUACUGGUCAAUGAAAACUUUUCAGAGGAAGGCAAACUGGUCAUUUAUACAAAACCGUUUGUGGAGCAUGUAGACUUCCUUUGCACUCACUAAGAAAGCACUCUUUUUAACGAGGGACUAUACAUUUGUUCAAUGAAAAGAAAAUAGCUCUUUGUACCUUGCUAACGGAAUUGCUAACUAUUCUUCAGAUAGGAGUCUCAUUGUUCCCACUAUUCAGUAUUUAAAUACACAUAAUGUCAUGUCUUUACUGCCAUUAGUCAGUAUUUUCAAAGAGCUCUUUUUAUUAAAUUUCUGAAACCCAGGACCAAAGAACACUUUCUCUUAGGUAUAUAUUAUUUGUUAGAAUGGAAACAAUCAAUACAUUUUCAGAGUCAAAAAGCACUGGGAAACAGUUUCUUUUUUGGUCUGAGCAUAUUUUUUAUUAAAAAAAAAACCUUUGAAAUAUUUUGUUUUAUCAGAAUUGUUUGUAGGGAAAAUGUAAACCUCACUAUUGUUUAACUGCAGUCCAAAGAGGACUAUCAUAUUGCACUUCUAAUCAAAAAAUAAAUUGAACAUAGUGGUAGGCUUACAGAAAGAGAGAGAAUUAGAUUUGAUUAGAUUAGCUUUAACCUGCCCGGAAUAAAACUGUCUGCCUUUCCUGUUAUUUGUCAGUGUUUAUAGCGGGUUUCAUCUACAAUGCUUUCACUAUUAUUUCUGGGCGGUAAAAGGCAGUCAAGCAGAAAAGACACUCAUAAAUGUCAGAAAAGAAGAAAGUCUGUGAUUGCUGUGAGCUUCAUAGCAGCGUUCCUUUUCCUGCUGGUUGUGCGUCUUGUAAAUGAAGUGAAUUUCCCAUUGCUACUAAACUGCUUUGGACAACCUGGUACAAAGUGGAUACCAUUCUCCUACACAUACAGGCGGCCCCUUCGAACUCACUAUGGAUACAUAAAUGUGAAGACACAAGAGCCUUUGCAACUGGACUGUGACCUUUGUGCCAUAGUGUCAAACUCAGGUCAGAUGGUUGGCCAGAAGGUGGGAAAUGAGAUAGAUCGAUCCUCCUGCAUUUGGAGAAUGAACAAUGCCCCCACCAAAGGUUAUGAAGAAGAUGUCGGCCGCAUGACCAUGAUUCGAGUUGUGUCCCAUACCAGCGUUCCUCUUUUGCUAAAAAACCCUGAUUAUUUUUUCAAGGAAGCGAAUACUACUAUUUAUGUUAUUUGGGGACCUUUCCGCAAUAUGAGGAAAGAUGGCAAUGGCAUCGUUUACAACAUGUUGAAAAAGACAGUUGGUAUCUAUCCGAAUGCCCAAAUAUACGUGACCACAGAGAAGCGCAUGAGUUACUGUGAUGGAGUUUUUAAGAAGGAAACUGGGAAGGACAGAGUCCAGUCUGGCUCAUAUCUCAGCACAGGGUGGUUUACCUUCCUUCUGGCCAUGGACGCCUGUUAUGGCAUUCACGUCUACGGGAUGAUAAAUGACACCUACUGCAAGACAGAAGGGUAUAGAAAAGUCCCCUACCAUUAUUAUGAACAAGGAAGAGAUGAGUGUGAUGAAUAUUUUCUUCAUGAACAUGCCCCAUAUGGGGGUCAUAGGUUUAUCACUGAAAAGAAAGUGUUUGCUAAAUGGGCCAAGAAGCACAGGAUAAUAUUUACACAUCCAAACUGGACAUUGUCUUGAUAAUGGUUUUCCUGAUCUUGCCGCAUCACUUAAUGUGAUCCCCAUACUGCAACUGUGAUGCUGAUGAUGCUAAUGGAGAUGAUGGUAAUGAUAAAGACAACAACAAUGAUUAUCAAGUUCCUGUACACUCUCAGAUGUGGAUGGUGACUCUGCUAGUAAUUUAAACUUGGCAUUUCAUGGAGGAUGGUUGUGCUCAUGAUGUUCUUUCUGGAGGUUCAACACUACGUACCGCACUUUAUAAUUUAACUGGAAUUGAGAUGAAGGCCAGUGACAUGACAACUGUGACCUAAGAAAUGGGAAGAUUAUCUUUCAAGAUAGCUGCCUAGAAUUGUUCAACAGUGAGUAACUUCCAGAAGCCAAAAGAGUUUGGCUUCAUGAGGCAAGGUGAUUGACUCAAUGGCUUGUUGAAUCUCAGCAGUUCCGCCAUCUUGAAGAAUGAUUGAUUGUCAAACACUGACCCAAGAACUGCUAUCAGGGUGCAAGUAUCUUACUACUUAGCCUAAGGAUGGGAAAAUAUCUCUUCCUAAUAUACCAUCUUUCUACAGUAUUUCCUACAGCUAAAGCCUCAGGCCAUUGCCUAAUUAACAAUGAAGAUUUCAUGGACAUCCUACACUUCAGGAUUACUUGACUAUCUCAAACACAUAAAUCAAAAUGGGCCAAGUAGCAAAUCUUGAUGAAUUUCCACUCUUACCAUCCAUUCUUACUACCAACAGUAUAACUGAACAUGUGAUUAGAAUGAUCUAUAUUAAUGUUUAGUUAUUUUUGGUUGAGUGCUAAAUAUUUCAGAAGGCUACUUAACAUGUAAGAUACCAACUUCAACACUGUAAUAACAUAUACUGUGAAAACAUUCCUAAAAAGUAACCAAAGGGUUUGCUAACUCUGCUUCAACAUCCAACAACACAAAACUAUAUGAUUUUUAAAAUCAUGAAAUAGAGACAGCAAAGCAUAUUUUUACAUCAAUUUGUAUCCUAUCAUACUUCAUAAUAUAUAUUUGUAUAUUCAAAUUUCUAUUUUAUAGGCCCAAGGUGUGUUUCUCCAAACAUUACAUUCUCAUUGCCAAGUGCCAGCUGUUACACAUGGAGAGGAAAUGAUUCCUUAUAUUAAACCUGACCAGAGCUUUUUGCCUUCUAGGGAUUUAUUUUUCCCAUAGUGUAUCAGUUGUUAUGCCACAAUAACAACAAUAAUAAUGUUCUUAAUGUCCAAAGUGCUUUGUCAUUUAGAGUCCUUUAACAUCUGUUAUACCAUGUGAUGCCCUUGAACACCCCAUUGGGCUAUUGUCUGUGUAUUCUGCUCUCUUUAGCAGAUGAUCUGUAAUUUGGUCAUUGUUCUGUUAUAUUCCAGAUUGCUCUACUUGCUAAUAUUUGUAUAGAAUAGAAUUUAUGUAAACUAGUAACCAGUUGAUCUCUGUGCCAAAUACAUUAUAUCAGGAUUACACAAAAAGUAUCACAAAGGAUGGUCUUGGCCAUAUGCUAGGGCCCCUGUGAAAAUAAGUAGUUUUGAGAAGUUUUUCUAUAUACGUAUAUAUACACGUGUGGUUCUAUUUAGGUGGGGAAAAAAUGAAAAAGCAGGGACAACAGGAGGAAAUGAAGGCAGAGAAAUAUAGUUUCCUUUCCUAGGAUUGAGACAAUUCUAUUUUUCAUAUACUCGUUGCUCAUUAAAUAGUAAAGGGUUGAUUUGCUGCAAGAGUAGCUGAGAAUUCAAAAACAUCCUUGCAGAAUGAUUCAAAAGACAAAAGCCAGGCUCAACUUAUAGAAUGUUUUGGAAACUGGAAGUAAUGAUACAUUUCACUUCAGAAGCACUUGUAGGUCUUUACUAGUGCUAAGUAUUAUGGUGAGCUAUCAUUAAAGUGUGCCAUCUUGGAUAAAGGCCUUUUGCCUACUCUCUUCUGCAAUUUUGACACCUCAAUAUUCACACCCAUAAACAUUACUAAGCCCCAGUUCUAUCGUUGGAAGGAGUUGUUAUUCUUUUGUUGUUCCCUUAUGCAAUUUUUAAUUCUAUGAAUGUUAAGUUUUUUUGAGCUAAUGAUAGAUAGAAAUGCCCACUCAAAGAAAAAUAAACAGAGACAAAUGUUAAAAUUGCCAUACAGACUGUUUUUCCCCCUGUUGUUUCACUUUAAAAUAAAAAGAAAUCCUUGAUUAAUCAGAAUGGCUUGGGACAUGAACUUAAUUUAUUUAGUUUUCUAAUAAAUGAAGGGCCAACUCUUAUUUGUUCUAGCCCCUACUGAUGAGAAACAUUUGAAAACUUGCUUGCUCUCCUGCCUCGUUGUAGCUUUCUCUGAUGAAGACUUCUGCAGUAUAUUGUAUCCCUCACUCUAUAGCAGAAGGUGUGUGUGGAAUAUGUAGACUCCAGUGUUUUCUUAGGAGGGGUGGGAAAGGGCUUUCUUUCCUCUCCUCUCCUCUCGUCUCCUCUUUCUUUCCUUUCUUUUUGCAACUAAACUGCUACUCUACACUUUUUAUUGUUGUUUUCUUUGUCUUUUUCUUUCUACAAACAGGAAACAAAAAAAAAAAAAAACAAGUUUUUCUCAAUUUGGAGACUCAAUUGAAUAAUUUCCAGUAUAAUCAGCAUUUUGAUAGAAUCUCACAACUUAUUUUUCUCUGCUUUUAUUUCCUGUUUUUCUUUGUUCCAUCUUUCUAAUUCUAGUGAAAAUGCAAAGUCUAAUUUCUCCCAUGUUGAGAAUAAAUUUUUCAUCUAUGAUUUGCUGAUAGAGAAGAGCUUGGUAAGGGAGCAAUUCAAGGAAACUAUUUUGCCAUGCACAUUUCUGAUCAAUUCCCACAGAUUCUGGUCAAAUGAAAGAUAUUCUAUCCAACAUUUAAACAUUGAAAAAUUUAACUGAACUUACUUAUCACUGAUGUGUAUUUAUCCCAGAAAUUAAUUAAUAUCUGUGAAAAAUAAAAAUAUUUCAAUACUAUCCGUGCUUCUUGGAAAAUGAACUAUAAAAAAGGGUCACAAUUUUUCUGAAAUUGGCAUGAAAACAUUCAAGAUAAAAAUAAUAGACUAAACAUUAUUUUCUGUUAUGCAUAAUUCUAUGAAAAAGCAAGGUAAUUUAAAAAGAGUUUUAAAAUGUGUGUUUGAAUCUUUUCCAAUUUAACCAAGUGAGAAGUAGCAAUGAUUUACAUUGUUAUGAUGAUAAUGUGAAUAAGAAACCUUUUAGAGUAUAUGAUUUUACAUUGCUAUCAAACCUAUCAAAGAAAAGGCAAUUGGAAUUUGGAGGAAUGUUUGUAUAUAUGCACAUAGAGUCUAUUUGUGUGUGUGUGAACGCACAUAUAUAUACAUCUAUAUACUUAUAACUAUAUAUAAAAGCAUAUAUAUAAUCCUAUAUUCUUCACUGGUGCAUGUGAAUCACAGAAAGCCCUAUUUUAGACUUCAUCUGAAAUUCGUUGGGUUACAUUUUGAAUCCUGAUGAAAAAAGCAAAAAUCCAAAUUAAAUGGACUGAUUGCUAAGAGUACGUAAAAUCAUAUUCAAAAGCUGGCCAGAAGAAUAAAGCUAGAGAAGCUGCUAAAUCUAGAAAACACAAUCAGAUGCCACAGUUGUCACAAAUCAGACUUGUAAGUAUAGCAAUCUGUAUUGUAGGUUCUGCCGAUUGCAGGCUUAGCUAAAGUCACAUUGAAAAACAUUGCAUCAAGCUUCAUUCACACUGAAGUAAAUGAACAUUGGUCCUCCUAUUCAAAUAAGCCAGUCUUUAGCAUAAGCAAAAUCCAGAUUUGCAUGAUUUUUAUUAUAUAGCUACAGAACUGUGACCACUGUGAAAAAGGAAAAUUAUACAAGGAGAUUGCUCUUGGAGGAUUUGGUAUGAAUCAGCUGAGGUAGGAACAAGAGUCUGAAUUGGGGACCUGCUGACCUUCCAAGAAGUAGAAGGCCAUCAGAAGAAAAUCACUGUUACUUAGAGAAGAGACAACACUAAAGUACUUCACCUGGUAGUGUUAAUUGGAUGUUAAUUAUGAGCUCGGUUUAAUUUCAAUAAGCAAGAAAAUAUAAUCAGAUGACUGAUUUAAAAAAAAACAACAACAAUGUGCCCAUCUAGCCUUUAAUGUGACAUGUCAAAUGCAAAUAAUAAAUUAUGUUAUUCAGUAUCAGUUGUUUGCAUGUCUUAGCACAACAAAGGAUUUACAGUCUGAGGGCCAAGAGAGAAAAAAUGCUUUUUUCUUAAAACAGCAUAUUUAAAAGACAAGACCUCAUCAUUUCAGUAGUGUACAUAGAUUAGUGACUGAAGGAGCCAGUGCUAGCCUUUUUAAGUAGGUCAGGCUUUUAGAGCUGAAAGAGAUUUUAAAGACCAGCCAAUUCAACUCCUACACCUUGGAGCUGAGGAAACAGACAGAGGUGAAGUGACUUGCCUGUAGUUAUAAACUGGACUAAUGGCAGUACUGAGACUCAAAUUCUUGUCUCAUGUUUUCUUCUCUAGUGCUUUUUCCACUACACUUUUUAGACAGAAGAGUAGCUGGAAAAAGAAUGCCUAACUGAUUUACUAAAGAGUCUAUUCAUGGAAUCCAAGGGCUCCAAAUUGUGCUAAUUCUGCUCAGGAUGAAACAAAUCCCCACGCUGAAGUGGAGAAAUAUUUUCAUAAUUGAAGGAACAUAUCCCAUUGAUUGUCUACACUUUCUUCUCUCUGUUUGUUGCUAUUGGUAAGGCUAGGCUAUGUUCUGUUAUCACAAAAUUCUAGGACUUGUUUAAAGAACUUAAAGGUCAGUUUCUUAGUUUCUCUUUGUGAUUGAGGAUGAGCAAGCCAUUGAUACACCAAGAGCUGCUGAGUGUUGGAGGUUGCCUGGUGAAACUGGCAGGCCCUGUUGUUGACAUUUCCCCAGAGCUAAAAUGUCCUCAUACUCAAACCAACUGUGCUGCCCAAGUUAGUGAAAUUAUCCAUCAGCACUAACACCACCCUUUGGGUUCAUGCUCAUCCCUGCACUCCAUGUGACCUUUGAGCCCAGAUACCCUUCUAGAAGGUGAAUGAAAGCCCCACAUGUCCCGCAAGACUUAGUCUGCAUAAAAGAUUUAAAAGGAUUUUUUUUUCUCUACAGUCCAUUUAUAUGAUACUGUUAGAAGUGAAGAAUUUUGAAACUACAUACACUGGCCUCUGAAAAUGGUUCUUGUGGCUCAGAAAUAGUAUAUUGUUCUGUUGCUUGUUUUUGCUGAACUGUAGAGAAAACACCAGAGUAAAAUUCCAUGUAAAUUGCUAAGGCAUCGAAUCAGAACUGUCCUUGGGCGUUGUAACAGUGCAGAAAAUCUCAUUUAGUUUUUUUCUUUUUUUUUUUCAGUUAACUACUUGUUUGUUUCUUUUCAGAAUAGGCACUUUUUUUUGAGUAGAAAACCUCUUCUUUCUCCACAGAUACAUCUCUUUUUGUUCACGCCUUGAAGACUUCAGAAAAAUAGAAGCUCACUUCCUUCCAUAAAGGUGAAGAACAUCUUGAUGAAUAAACAGUCAACUACCAAGUUCACAUAUUUGCCUAUGAAGUGAGAGCUAUUUCUAAGAAACUUCAAAAAGAUCAAAACGAGGCAAUUUUAUAGCUUUUUGUUACCUAAUCUACAAAGUACUAAUUUCCUUGUGUUUAGCUUUGUUGUCACUGUUACUGAGUAAAUACCCAUUUCUGUUACAUAUGGUACAUUUUUUGCUUCACUUAUUUUCCUGAGUUCCCAUGAUUUUUUUUCUGUAGUUUCUCAUUCAUUUUAAAACCCAUAAUCUUCAUCUAUUUUUAGAAGAAAGUGUAAAUGCACAGUUGUACGUUUGUUGAGAGUUUUUAUGGCAUUAUAGUGCUUUAUUUAUAAGCAUUGUGUCUUAGAAUAAAGCUUACAAAAUGGCAAAGA